AGUUCCGACGAAAAAUGGCGGGGUCUCCUGAGUUGGUGGUCCUUGACCCUCCAUGGGACAAGGAGCUCGCGGCUGGCACAGAGAGCCAGGCCUUGGUCUCCGCCACUCCCCGAGAAGACUUUCGGGUGCGCUGCACCUCGAAGCGGGCUGUGACCGAAAUGCUACAACUGUGCGGCCGCUUCGUGCAAAAGCUCGGGGACGCUCUGCCGGAGGAGAUUCGGGAGCCCGCUCUGCGAGAUGCGCAGUGGACUUUUGAAUCAGCUGUGCAAGAGAAUAUCAGCAUUAAUGGGCAAGCAUGGCAGGAAGCUUCAGAUAAUUGUUUUAUGGAUUCUGACAUCAAAGUACUUGAAGAUCAGUUUGAUGAAAUCAUAGUAGAUAUAGCCACAAAACGUAAGCAGUAUCCCAGAAAGAUCCUGGAAUGUGUCAUCAAAACCAUAAAAGCAAAACAAGAAAUUCUGAAGCAGUACCACCCUGUUGUACAUCCACUGGACCUAAAAUAUGACCCUGAUCCAGUUCUCAACGGGAAUGCUUUCAACUUUUCCCCAUUCAACAUGAUGUUGGCUGUGGAUUUGUCAUAUAUGGUUUUUAUUACUUCGAGCCCCUCAUAUGGAAAAUUUGAAAUGCAGAGGGGAAACAGUAGCAAAGGAGAUCAGUGAAGCCAUGAAGUCCUUGCCUGCAUUAAUUGAACAAGGAGAGGGAUUUUCCCAAGUUCUCAGGAUGCAGCCUGUUAUCCACCUCCAGAGGAUUCACCAAGAAGUCUUUUCCAGUUGUCAUAGGAAACCAGAUGCUAAACCUGAGAACUUUAUAACACAGAUAGAAACCACACCAACAGAGACUGCUUCCAGGAAAACCUCUGACAUGGUACUGAAAAGAAAGCAAACUAAAGACUGCCCCCAGAGAAAAUGGUAUCCAUUGCGGCCAAAGAAAAUUAAUCUUGAUACAUGAGCUCUUUCUGUUUAUUUUGGGAGUUGAAAAUAGGCACCAUCAACAUUUAGAUUACAGCCUAAUUAAUACCUAGAUAAGACUUCAUUUGAAAUAAGAAAUAACUCUUUUACUAGUGAUUCAUUUAUACAGAUAUAGUAUCUCUGUGCGGGGAUAUGAUAUAAUAUUGUAUUUCCUUACUGUUUUAUCUAUUGUAAAUAAAAAGCAUUUUAAAAAGUAUUGACACAAAGCCCAUCAGUGGGCAUUAAAAAUAUUAAAAGUGCAGACUUUUACUGUCCUUAAGUGCCAUCAACUCUCAGCUCCCUUGUAGCUUUUGUGGGAUUUAACAAGUAACAAAUUCUGUUGUGUUUCCCUGGUAUACAUCUUUCUAGGAAAAAAAAAAAAAAGAGAGAGAGCUGUAUAAUGAUUUUUCGUUUACAUGCUGAAAAGUAAUUAUCAGUUCUGCACAGCAGCAGAUGCAGGGUUUUUUUUUAAAGAUGUAGUUUGAUUUAUCAAAUUAAUGUGCUGAUGAUAAUACUGGCUUUGACUUUGUUACUCCAUGUUCAGCUAAUUUAGGUUUGUGAGAUUAACUUUAGGAUUUUUUGUUGUGUAAGACAAUGAUAACUAUUAUUUGUGCAACAUUACUCUUUGAAAUAAAAAUUGGCAUGUAGCCAAUGUUUCCUGCCCACACUCACUUUUUUCUAUAGACCAUUAACAUAAUUUGACUUGGAACUAAUGGUUUCUUUUUAGGGUUUCUUAUUUAUUUCUUUACAAAUCAUUCCAGUUCAAAAUAUAUAUCAGAUUAAUACACUGGCAAAGUGUCAUUGUGUUAUUGAACUAUUUCACAUUUGAAGAUGUUUAUAUAUCAGGUAUAUAAUCACUGGGAGAAGUCUGAGAAAACGAUAUUGGCUUUACUUCUAACAUUUAACUAUAGUUUCUUAUAGCUCUUAUUGUGUGUCUUACAUUAUACAGUGUAGGCAGGGCCAUCAAACUUACCAACUGUUUCCCCUUUUGAUGACUCUGAUACCUUCAUUCAUUUUUCAAAGGAAUUUACUGAUCAUGAGGUUGGAAAAUCUGUAUUUCUCUUGCUUAUUAUGUAUUAAUAAUCAUAAAUGUCUAGAUUCACCAGAAGUCACCAGAAGGUCUGUCUCAGUGAAGAAAACUUAUAAAGCCACUUUGUUGCAUUUUGUGUUUCAGUGUUACAGUUUGAGAUCUGUAUAUUUGUACACAGCUAUGUGUUUUUCAUUGAAAUAAUGUACAAAGACUGAUCUUGAUGCUGUGUAUUUUUAUGAGUUGUCUUAGGCAUUCCUGAGCUCAGCUUCAGUUGGAUGGUGGGUCAGCACCCUGCGUUUCUGAACAUACUAGACUUCAGUUUAAAACUGUUUUGAGGCUGUAUAAUAUGUUGCUGUUUUUACAGUGCUAAUGUUUUUAUAGUAUUAAAAUUCUGUAUGAUUUGUUUCACUUCAGAGGUCCCCAAACAAAAGAGUUAUUGUUAAUUCUAUUAGAUUAUAUAAGCUACUUGCAUUUUGAUUAUAUAAGAACAUGGUCCCUCCCUUUUAAGAGAGGUAUAUUGUGCUACAUAGAGUUUUUAAAUGACAUGAUAGAUUUGCUCUGAAGUAUUCAGCAGAGAAACAAGGAAUCGAUUAAGGAAAUGUGACAAAAAUCCUGUUAAUGUUGAAUCUGUGUAAUGACUAUAUUCUACUUUGUGUUGGAAAUUUUUAUAAGUUUUUAAAAAAUGGUUAUAUUUUAAAGUCCCCAGGCAGACAGCUGAGAUUUGAAAUCCUCUUGAGAGCCCAAAGUUUUACUCCAUAGUUAUAGCAGAGUUUAAAAUAGAAAUACCACUGGGAAAGACAGUACGUAUUAGCAUUAUUAACUAAGAAAAGCAUGACCAAUAGCAGUAAUAAUAUUGAAUAAGUAUACUGUGUAAGAGGAGAAGUUGCAUUUCUGCAUAGGCCAAGAACUAGUAAGCUAAGGAUUAAAAGCAAGAAAGUCUGUAGUUUUAAGGAAUUGGAAAGGUUGAAGGAAAAAAUUGAAAAUCAAAUCUUGCUCUAUGAUAAAAAGAGUCUGGAUUGAAUAGGGUCUUAAAAUUAUCUUUCAGAAAAGAAAUAGCCAGGCGCGGUGGGCUCAUGCCUGUAAUCCCAGCACUUUGGGAGGCUGAAGUGGACAGAUUACUUGAGCCCAGCCUGGGCAACAUAGUGAAACUCCAUUUCUACAAAAAAUACAAAAAUUAGCAGGGUGUGAUGGCACACACCUGUAGUCCCAGCCACCCAGGAGGCUGAAAUGAGAGGAUCACUUGAGCCCUGGAGGCAGAAGUUGCAGUGAGCCAGGAUGGCACCACUGUACUCCAGCCUGGGUGACAGAGUGAGACCCUGUUUCAAAAUAAUAAUAAGAAGAACACAAGAAGGUUAAGUCUAGUCCCAAAGAAGAGAGAACACUGUCAAAGCUGGUUUCUGAAAACUGGUACCAAAAUCUACAUUUGUUUAUUUAGGCUACUAUAACAGAAUACCACAGGCUGGGUGGCUUAAACAACAGAUACUUACUUCUCACAGUUCUGGAGGCUAGAAGUCCAUGAGAAGGUGCUGGCAAAUGCAGUUUCUGGUGAGGGCUGUCUUCCCGACUUGUAGAUGACCACCUCCUUACUAUGUCCUCACAUGGCCUUUCCUCAGUGCAUGCAUGUGGAGAGAGGGACAGAGUGCAAGCUCUCUGGUGUCUCUUCUUAUAAGGACACCAAUUGUAUCAGAUCAGAGCCCCACCCUUAUGGCCUCAUUUAACCUUAAUUAUUUCCUUAGAGGCCCCAUCUCCAAAUACAGCUAUAGGCACAUGGGAGUUAAGGCUUCAUCAUACAGAUUUUAGGGGGACACAAACAUUGAGUCCAUAACACAAGCCCACAGAAAAUCUUAUCCUAGACCUCUUUCCCUGGCCCUUUAUGGCUUGGGCUCCGUAGAGGACAAAGUGAAUAAAACCAAAUUUUUUAUUGCUUCAAACAGUAUGAUUUCAUCUUGUAAGAUGUACUUUUUCUUUUCUAAGGCUGAAUUUGUUUGAUUUCUGGUGAACACCUAUCUUCUCUAUCCACCUUCAUUCAUUUAUUCAUCUGUUCAACACAUACAGUUGGACACCUACUCGGAUCAAAAGUCAGAGAUCUUAAGAGCACAGCCUCUAAGCCAGAUCAUCUGAGUUCAGAUUUCAGUUCUACCAUUAUUAGUUCAAUGAUAUUGGACAAGUUACUUAACCUGUCUAUGAUCAAAAGUCAGAGAUCUUAAAGAGCAUAGUCUCUGAGCCAGAUCAUCUGGGUUCAGAUUGCAGUUCUACCAUUAUUAGUUCAGUGACAUUGGGCAAGUUACAUAACCUGUCUAUGCUGCAGUUUUCUCAUGUGCAAAAUGGGGAUAAUAAUUAUGCCUACCUCAUAGCGUUAUUCUGAGAAGUAAAUGAGUUCAUAAUGUGAAGGCCUUAGACUAAUAACUGGUGCAUAUGAGUACUCUAUGAUCACUGUUAUUACUUCUUUUGAUAAAGGAAAUGAAAACACUCAGGACAAGUGUUGCCUUCAGGAAGGUCAUAUUCCAGUGAAGAGGAUGAGUGUGCAAACAAUGAUAAUGCCAUGCAGCAAAUGGUAUGAUAGAUGUAUGUGUGGAACUUAGGGGAGUAGUCAUGGAAGUCUUUGUAGAAGAGGUGGCAUUUGAGCAGUCUUGAAUGUUUUAGGCAAAUAAUCAGGGAAGGAAUACAGGAAUAAAGAACAAAUUACUGUUAUAACAAUGUGGAUCAAUAUCAAAGAUACUAUAUUGAAUAAAAGAAGCAAAGCCAGGCACAAGAGAAUACAUCCUGUGUAUGGAAUCACAGAAUGGGCAAAACUAAGCCAUGGUGGUUCCCUCUGGGGAGAGGGGAGAUAUUAACUGGGAAUGGCACGGGAAACAUUUUUGGGUGAGCAAAAUGUUCUGUAUCUUGAUCUGAGUGGUGCUCACAUGGCUGUAUAUGUAUGUAAAAUUUUGUUGAACUAUACACUUAAAAUUUCUGCACUUUAUUUAAGUUUUAUAUUUUAAAAAUGCACAAAACUGAUUCACCAAAUAUUUGAGGAGCGUCUCCAGCAUCAAAGACAGACCCAAAAACUGUAAGUCCCUUAAUGGCAGGAAUCUUUGUUCCAUCCACCUGGAAUAAUUGCUGGCACAUGAUGGGCCCUCGAUGCAUAGUGGUUAACUGAGUGAAUUAAAACAAAAACCAAAGAGAAUAAAGGACCUCAAAGAAAACAGAUACAUACAAAGCAAAAUCCCAGAAUGAUGACUGUACUCCCAGAAAGAAGAGAAAAUCAUACAUUUUUUGGAAAAUCGGAAUGCUAUUAAAUAAUGUUCAGUAAAUAAGAAAAAGUUUUUGAAAAUUAAAAAUAUGAAAGUUGAAAUAAAAAUUCAGUGGGAGGGCUGGGAGAUAAAAUGAAAUUUUCCCAAAAAUAAAACAGAAAGAUUAAGAAAUGGCAAAUUAGAAAAGUAAGAAUAAAGAGAAUAAGUUCAUAAAGUUCAAAGUCUAAUCGAUACCCAUUCCAGAGAUAGCAUGCAGAAAAAGCAGCAGAGUCAAAAUUAUCAAAGAGAUAAUGCAGUUACCAUAUGGCCCAGCAAUUUUACUCCACGUUCUAAACCUAAGAGAAUUGAAAACAUGCUCACACAAUAACUUACACACAAAUGUUUGUAGCAGCAGGUUGAACUUUCAUGAACUGAUGAAUGGAUAAAUAAAAUGUGGACUAUCCACUCAAUAGAAUAUUAUUUGGCAAUAAGAAGAAAUGAGGUACUGGUAAAUGCCACAGUGUAGAUGAACCUUAAAACAUGCCAAGUGAAAGAAGCCUCUCACAAAAGACUGCUGAAUUUUGUAGACUCCAUGUAAAUGAACUGUCCAGAACAGGCAAAUCUACAGAAACAAAAAAUAGAUCUGUCACUGCCUAAGGCUGGAAAGAUGGAGAGGGUGGAAGGAAUAGGAAGUGACUGCUAAUGGGUAUGGGAUUUUUUUUUUUUUUUUUUUGUGAAACAAGGUCUUGCUGUGUUGCCCAAGCUGGAGUACAGUGGUGCUAUCUUGGCUUACUGCAACCUCUGCCCCCGCAACUCAAGCCAUCCUCCCACCUUAGCCUCCCAAGUAGGUGGGACUAUAGGCAUGCACCAUCAUGCCCAGCUAAUUUUUGUAUUUUUUGUAGAGACGGAGUUUCGCUAUGUGGCUGGUCUCAAACUCGUGAGCUCAAGCGAUCCGCCCACCUCUGCCUCCCAAAGUGCUGGAUUACAGGCGUGAGCCACUGCGCCUGGCCUGGGAUGUCUUUUGAGGGUGAUGAAAACCCUCUAAAUUUGAUUAUGGUGAUUCACGACUGCUUGUUGAAUAUACUGAAAACCAUUGAACAAUACAGUUUAAAAGGGUGAGUGAGAUGGUAAAGUAUAUCUCAAUUUAAAAAGAGAAUAAAGAAAUAGAAAUAACACAAGAAACAUUCCCAGACCUGAGGAAUACCAAGAGGAAUUGGAAUGGCAUCAGAUUACUAAACAACAAUCCUAAAAUCUAGAAGCAUCUGGAGAAAUAUUCUCAGCAUAAAUGAUAUACAACCUAGGCUUUUAUACACAGUCAAACUAAUAAUCAAGUGCAUGAUUAGCUAAAAGAUAUCUCAGAUAUGCAAAGCGUCAAAAAAAAUUACCUCCAAGGCAUCCCGUUUGGGGGUUCUACCAGGGGCUGUGCUCUAUUCCAAAGGGUAAACCAAAAAAGCAGCAGCCAUGGGAUCUGGGAAACUAAGGCUCCCAAAACACAGCACACUCGAGUCUACAGGCUACUAACUAAUCAGCAGAUUUGGAGACUAGGCAGACCAGGUUGGAAUAAGACUAUGUAGGCCGGGUGCGGUGGCUCACACCUGUAAUCCCAGCACCUUGGGAGGCCGAGACAGGCAGAUCACCUGAGGCUGGGAAUUGGAGACCAGCCUGACCAACAACUAAAAAUACAAAAUUAGCUGGGCGUGGUGGCGCAUGCCUGUAAUCCCAGCUACUCAGGAGGCUGAGGCUGGAGAAUCGCUUGAACCCAGGAGGCAGAGGUUGCAGUGAGCCAAGAUCACGCCAUCGCACUCCAGCCUGGGCAACAAGAACGAAACUUCAUCUCAAAAAAAAAAAAAGGACUAUGUAGGACUCCAAAAGAGAUAUUUUCAGAAAAAAAUAAAAGUGACAACACGAGUGAUAAUGUUAACUAUGCAGAAAAUUGUAUAAAGGAGAUGUUUUGUAAUAUGAUUAAGAUGUUCAAAGAAACAAAAAAUAAGGCAGUUAUUCACUACAGUAGAGGCAGAAAGCUGUACAAAAAAAGAAAUGUAAUCAUGGUUACAAAUUAGUUCUCCAGUGAACAAUAUUUAUAUAGCCAUAAUAAUAAAAACCCUGAAUCUGAAUUCAGUAAAAAAAAAAAAAAAAAAUUGGGACAGUUACACUGGGAGGCUAAAGGAUGGGAAUUAGCAAUUAGUACAGCACAGGCACUGAACAGUUAGAUGGACAUUGGUUAAAGCAGUAAGGUGGGGUGUGGAGGCCCUUAUAGCUGCUGGGUCCUGGGGCAGGGUAGGGUGUCCCAGGACAUGGAGCUGGAGCAGCCAGAGUGGCAGGGAUAGUGAGGAGGCUUCUGUGCCAACCAGUACAAUCCAUAUGUUUGUAACAGUGUGACUGUCUGAACACCAGCUUUGACAUGGCAGUGGGGAGUGAAAUCUUCACCCACCACAACUGGAAGUCAGUGGAUGUCUAAAAAGCUGAUUCAAGAUCAUACAAUAUGGAUAUAAUUUAGUGCAGCAGAAUAAAGAGCUGACGAAGUGGGAAGUAUUAACUCUGUGGAUGAACUUAGGUGGGGGAACUGGGCCAGGGACUGAUAAUUUUUGAUAGAAGCCUCAUAGAUUUGAUUUUUAAAAUUAAAUGCAUAUAGUAAUUAAGGGAAAAUAAAUUUGGUUUAAGAGACAAAUCAUCCCCUAGAACCUUUCUCGGGGUUUCAGUUUUUCAGGGUUUCAGAAGCUUUCUCAGGGUUUCAAAACAGGCGUGUGCCACCAUGCCCGGCUAGUUUAUUUGUUUUAGAGAUGGGGUCUCGCCAUAUUGCCCCGGCUGGUCUUGAAUUCCUGGGCUCAAGCCAUCCUCCUGCCUCAGCUUCCCAAAGUGCUGGGAUUACAGGAAUGAGCCACUGCACCUGGCCUAUCACAGUAUAUUUCAGAUAAGACUUACUAUUCUCUGUUUUUGGCUGAUAAUUCUAGUUUUGGUUUCUUCAGGUUUUUUUUUUUUUCUCCCCUCUGACCAUUUGUUUUGCAAAUAGAUUAUAUUAUGAAAGUCUCUGAAGAAAAAAAUAUCUCUCUAGAGAACCACUGAAGGGGGUUCUUGGGGAUUUUAUAUGAAAGGAUUUGAGAAAAUUAAUGUUAUAUUCAUUUGAAGCUUCAGGGGUAAAGAAUCCCUUGUAAUUCGUUGCUGUGUCUCUACAUUGCUCAUACUUUGCCCAUGGGCUGUAAACUAAUAUUCGUUGAAUGAAUGAGUUCAUAUUGCAAAUUUCUAACUUGUCGGUUUCCCUGGAUCACAAUCUCACACAUUAAUGGCUUGUGGCAUUUAUAUUCAUUAUUAAUUGAACUUAGAAGGUGAGUGUGGGGAGGGGAGAGGUAAAAAACUGAGGACAGAUCACUGGGAAACUGACCUGAAUUAGGACUCCAGAGUCUCCUGUCUACUAGAACUACGUCUACUAGAACUAAGUCUAAUUCCCAUAUCCCUGCAGGACAUAAGAGCAGAGGAUGGCAUUGACAUCCCUCAGUGACAUCACUGUGCUAGCAGGUAUAGUUGCCUUCUGAUCACCUUUUCCUUUGGUCACAUCCCCUGACUUCUGGGUGGCCUGGGAUAGCUAGAGAAGAAAAUUCAACUUCUCCCUGCAGGUCUUCUGCUCCAGCUGACUCCUGUGCCUGUGUAAAAGAUUGGGCAUUUCUAUCAUCACCUUGACUAGCCUUACUCAGAGAAUGGCUCCAGUGCCUUUGGGCUCAUACCUAGUUGCAGAUUUUAAGACCUCCCUUGGUGCCCAUUCAUGUAGCUCUGUGGCCCACAUCUUCUACAAUGAUGUCAUUGGAGUUCUUUUGUCCAUUUCUGCCCCUGAUGCCACCUUGAUGGGAAUGCCACCCUCCACACAACUCUUCACCAGUCCAUAAAUACCUGAGACUUGGCGCAUUUCUUUUUUUUUUUUUUUUUUUUUUUUUUUUGAGACUGUCACCCAGGCUGGAGUGUAGUGGAGCGAUCUCAACUCACUGCAACCUCCACCUCCCAGGUUCAAGAGGUUCUCAUGCCUUAGCCUCCCGAGUAGCUGGGAUUACAGGCGCGUGCUACCAUGCUGGGCUAAUAUUUGCAUUUUUAUAGAGAUGAGGUUUUGCCAUGUUGGUCAGGCUGGUCUCGAACUCCUGACCUCAGGUGAUCCACUCGCCCUGGCCUCCCAAAGUGCUGUGAUUACAGGAGUGAGCCGCCACGCCCGGCCCAUUUCAUUCUUAAAAAAAAAAAUCCUUCCGGAGGUUUAGUUCCUCCACAAGGCAGCUUCUGGUUACCUGCCCCCUCAGGGUCCUUGCUGCCUGGGUCACCCCAGCAACCCCUUCGUCCACACAUCACUGCCCUUUGCAGCACCAGCUGAUUACAUUGCUUUUUCCAUGUUCUAGCUGUUCUUUUGAGCCGUUUUAUAGCCGAGCAUCUCCACCAGAAGAGCGGAUAGGAAAAAGGAAAAGAGAGGAGGAUUUGACCUUGGUAUCUUGCUUCAUUUCCUUCUCUGACAAAAAUUUGGUGAAAAGGUUAAAAUAAGUGUUCGAAUUCUCUCUGACUUGUCAUAUUCUGUCUAUGCCCUGUGUGCCUGCCUCUGAUCCUGAGGAAGUGUAGAAAUGAGGGGAUGACACUGGCAGAAUAAUAAAAAUGGGCAAAGUUGUAGGGCACCCCUGCUCCAGGUCCCAUACACCCCAGCUCCAGAGCCUCAGGAUCUUUCCCAGCCAUGUGCCAGACAAUAUUGUAAAAUGAUUUUUCGUAGCCACACCUUUUAUUACACACAUACUCGAUGAAUCUAAAUACUGUGCUAAGAGCUGUGUGGAUGUACACCUGUAAACCAAGGCACAGACCCUGCCCACAAGCAAUUUGCCGUCAGUUAGGGGAGCCAUCAGUAGCAUCUAGGGAUCCAUUAGAGGGAAAAGAGGGAGCUGAGGGAGAGGCUAGGAGCCCAAGCAAACCUGCACUUCUGCUCCUAGAGGGAACCUGAGAGUGAAACUCAUGGGUUUGGAAACUUCUGUGGAAUUACCUGCUUGCAAGAAAUGAUUUUGUCUGGUUUUAGAAACUACGAUGGAACACUAAUAUAUUCCUGUAAUUGACUGGCAAGUUUUAACACUUACUGCAAUUUAUUUUUCUUGUAAGCCCAACCCAAGUAUUCUUCCUUUAAAAAAAAUUUCAGAUUGACAAAUGACUGCUUCUUUAGAAAUCCUCCUUACUAAAAUUACUCCUCAUUUCUUUUUCUUUCAUAUUCAAAGGGAACAAACGUUCAAACACACAAAUAAACACUGCUCUUUGCCAGAGUGGUGGACUCUGGCCUCCCCACCCCCAGCACUCCCAGUCUUGCCCUCCUGCAAACACUAGACUUAAUUUUCUCUGCGCUGAGGGCCCUCCUCGAGUCAGAGUGAGAGGAAAAACAGAAGGGAGAAGCUGCGAGAUGUGGCAACAAAGGGGACGGUGAUCAGGUUUAUCCCUGAUGUUGUCUGUGAAGGUGUUCCAUUCUCCAGAGAUCUCACCAAAUGGUAUAAGUGAUGUGCAGAUAAGCCUGUGGUUCCCUUCACUCAUCAGAUCAGAGCCUCAGAAUUCUCAGAAACCAUUUUUUUCCUAACAUAAAACUCCUUUUCUCAUUUCUAUCCCUCUGUAAAUCUGAUUUGAAAAAAUUGUUUGAACAAACCAACAAUGUCAGAUUUGUUCCAGCUAUAUGAGCUCACAAUUCAUCUACUCUUGGUAGUUCAAGAUAAAAGAUUACCCAAAGAAAAGGAAGAGAUUGAGUAAAGCCACAACUGUAAUAGUGUCCCAGAUUGGGUAAAAGGCCAUUAAUAAAUAGCGUGAAUUGUAGAACUGUUUAAAGCAGCAUAUUUUUAAAACAGGCAUAUAAAGAAUCCACUUUAUGCCUGGAAUUGUACAAAAAUACUUUAAAUAAAUGUUUACAUAUAUAAUGUUAUCAACUUAUUUGCUGAAGGUAAUAUCAAUAUAAUGCUAGUAGUUACCAUGUAUUGAGUGCUUACUACAUGCCAUGAUCAUGCUAAAAGCUUCACAUGCACCAUCUCUUUUAAUCCUCAAGACAAUCCAUGAAUUAAGGGCUAUUACCACGCCCAUUUCAUGAGAAAGAGGUGGAGAUGAGAAGGGAAGUGCCUGGCCACCUUCCCAGCGGUCUAUAGACCAUGUAGAGCAGAGCGAGGCCUUCUGACCACAAACUCUGCUUCCACCUUCUCCCCGUGGUUCACAGCAAAGGCCUUGUCCAGAGUCUCAGACGCUCUCACCGCUACACCACAGCGACCUCGUUGGUUCUUCUCAUUUUUUUUCAAUGACACAUAGCAACAGAGAGUAUCAACAAACAUUUUUAAAUUUCCCAGCAGUUAACGAAUAGUGAAUAUUACUAUGUAAUACUAGUGUCUAAGAAAGUGCUCAAAGUUGUUUAAAGCAAUUUAUUAUCUUAAUGAGGUUAAAUAUGAACUUUUGCUGUUAAUUUCUUGGGAAAUAUAAAUCAUCAUAGCUAGUCAUUCUUUCAUCGUGGGAAGCUAACAGUCCUGAUUGUUCAGGAUUAUAAUUAUAGUAAAUUCUGAAUUUGUGACGUGUGAAUUUUAGAAGGUUACAAAACAACUUCCAGACAACUGAGUCAUAAAGUUUUUGAGAGAAGUAUGUGGCACACGUCUAAUUCAUUGUCCUUUCUCUCCAGUGGUAUAGUUAUGAUAUUAACCUAAAUUGCAAAAGGAAUCGUUUUAGUUGACUGCUGCUUGAAAUUGUGUCACUUUUCCAAAUUUAGGUAAUGUCUGUUACAAGGAGUAUAUUUUGGAAACAUUAACUUGACUGAUACUUAUUUCCCUGGUUAAGUGACCUUCCUGCCAUGUGCUGAGUGCCAGGACUUACUGCCCCUCAGUAAUUUGGAAGGGGAUCCUGGGCCCUGCCUGGAACAAAGGGUUGUGAAACAGCUCUGAGUCUCAAGGCAAGUCUUGAAAGCCAUAUAUAGUUUUCAGAAAAAGAGAUCUUCUAAAUUCCAUUCACCCCCAUUUAACACAUUAGGAGCCAAGCCUGGUGGACUAGCUCUAGGGGCAGUUUAGGAGAGAAGGGGAUCGGGGAACCUUCAUCCCUUCUGCCUCUGGUGAACUGGCAAGAUGAAGAGGAUGAAGCUGGGUGACCCAGAGCCCGCCCUCCCUCUCUCGGCAGUCAUCUCCAAGGCCGGAGUAGACUGGACUGGAGGGCCUCUGAGAGGACACAGCCAGGAAGCACACUCUCCCUGUGCUCUUCACCCACCAUGAAGAGACAGGACGGGAAAGUCCGUGCUGUGCUGGUGUCCAUCAGAGGGAGGGACACCAUCCAGCCCCUGGGACCGGGCUCGGCUCUGUUGUUGCACAGAAGUCAUUUGGAGAUCCCCACGUGCCACAUGGAGGAUUGUGGGAGGACCCCACCGAGGUGGCUGGCAGCCUCUCAUGGACACCAUGGAGAGUGACCCAAUCACUCUGCAUUUGAGGACUGCAGAGUGGCUCAGCGGUCUGGACAUUGAAGAGGAGCCAACCUCAGGGGUAACACAGUGCCGCUGGGAGCUGAGAUGAGCCAGGUGGUCGGUGGGGGACACAAGCCUAGAACAAAUUCAAUAAACCAGCCACAGACGUUAUCAUCAGAUGUGCCCAGAGACAAGGUGGACAGGGGCAUUUGCUGUGGAGACCAGAGGGCCAGAGAGAGUACAGGGACCUGGAUAGAUGGCUCCAGCACCUCUUCUUCUCCCUACACCCAUAUGCCAUCUUGAUAAACAGCAGGGAAAUCUGAAAAAUACCAAGUCUUCCCAUAGGGACAGUGUUACCUCCCAAAAACUGUUUGAAUAAUUGGCUUGAACUGGAUUUUCUGAACUGAACUAAUGCUAUUGUUUUGUGGGUUUUUUUCUUCCUACUGAGUAGAGUAGUUGUUUAUGGGGGACAUCUGAUCCUUUCAUUUUCUUCCAGAGAGCUAACCACCUGUUCUGACACCAUUUAUUGAAUAGUACCUCUUUUCCCCCACUGAUGUGAGAGGCUGCAUUUUUCAUCUAAUAAAAUCGAAUAUAUAUUUAGAUCUA